AUUCCACGUUCUUAACUGUUCCAUUUUCCGUAUCUGCUUCGGGCUUCCACCUCAUUUUUUUCGCUUUGCCCAUUCUGUUUCAGCCAGUCGCCAAGAAUCAUGAAAGUCGCCAGUGGCAGCACCGCCACCGCCGCCGCGGGCCCCAGCUGCGCGCUGAAGGCCGGCAAGACAGCGAGCGGUGCGGGCGAGGUGGUGCGCUGUCUGUCUGAGCAGAGCGUGGCCAUCUCGCGCUGCGCCGGGGGCGCCGGGGCGCGCCUGCCUGCCCUGCUGGACGAGCAGCAGGUAAACGUGCUGCUCUACGACAUGAACGGCUGUUACUCACGCCUCAAGGAGCUGGUGCCCACCCUGCCCCAGAACCGCAAGGUGAGCAAGGUGGAGAUUCUCCAGCACGUCAUCGACUACAUCAGGGACCUUCAGUUGGAGCUGAACUCGGAAUCCGAAGUUGGAACCCCCGGGGGCCGAGGGCUGCCGGUCCGGGCUCCGCUCAGCACCCUCAACGGCGAGAUCAGCGCCCUGACGGCCGAGGUGAGAUCCAGAUCCGACCACUAGAUCAUCCUUAUACCGACGGGGAAACGGAGGCCAGAGAGGGCGUGGGCGCUUGCACCACUUCCGUCCCAUCCUUGCGGGUACCUGGCUAUGCGGGGGUGCCUAAGGAGCCUGGAAAAAGCGCUCCCCCGUCGUGCUUCCUGGGGAAGGGGGCGUUCGCUGCGCUCGGAGCGGCGUCCCUUCCAACCCGCCGGUCUCAUUUCUUCUCGUUUUCACAGGCGGCAUGCGUUCCUGCGGACGAUCGCAUCUUGUGUCGCUGAAGCGCCUCCCCCAGGGACCGGCGGACCCCAGCCAUCCAGGGGGCAAGAGGAAUUACGUGCUCUGUGGGUCUCCCCCAACGCGCCUCGCCGGAUCUGAGGGAGAACAAGACCGAUCGGCGGCCACUGCGCCCUUAACUGCAUCCAGCCUGGGGCUGAGGCUGAGGCACUGGCGAGGAGAGGGCGCUCCUCUCUGCACACCUACUAGUCACCAGAGACUUUAGGGGGUGGGAUUCCACUCGUGUGUUUCUAUUUUUUGAAAAGCAGACAUUUUAAAAAAUGGUCACGUUUGGUGCUUCUCAGAUUUCUGAGGAAAUUGCUUUGUAUUGUAUAUUACAAUGAUCACCGACUGAAAAUAUUGUUUUACAAUAGUUCUGUGGGGCUGUUUUUUUGUUAUUAAACAAAUAAUUUAGAUGGUG